AGUCCCUAUUUGGAACUGCUCUCGCGGCAGUUCAGACCUCGUGCUCGUCCCCUUCGCCUGUCUGUGUGUGGUAUCCGUAGGUCCGGGGCACUUUUUUUUUUGGUGUGUGUGUGUGUGCGUGCGCGCGUGUGUGUGUGUUGGGUGUGUGUGUUUUGGGGGUUUGCCGGGGCGCGGAGAGGAGAGCCGGGCCGAGGGGAAGGAAGGAAGCCGUAGAGCUCCCCGGUCUCGGGCUGCGUCUCCCCUCCAGCGCUCUCCUGCCUGUGCGCUCCGACGCGGCAGCGGCGGUGGCGCUGAGCGCUCCUCGGUGGGGACGCGGUGCUCAAGCUGGGAGCAGCGAGAACCCUUUGCGGAGGCUUCCCGUGCCCGCUGGACUUAGGAUGCCAGGGCGUUUGAUUUGCACCUACUGAGCCCGGAGUUCCUCCCCGGCCCUGGGAAGGGCUUGCAGCGGCGGCGGCGGCGGCGGCAGCGGCAGUAGCAGACGGAACAGCAGGCUCUCCUCUCCGAGGGGGGGCGUCGAAGCGCCCGCGCCGGGCUCCCGCCCUCACCCUCCGGCGCUCCUGCGGCCCCAAGCCACCACCUCGUAGCCCGCCUCCUUCCUCUUCUCGCCGCGAGCCCCAGGCCCGGACGCCUCUAGGAUCGGACCCGCGCGCCCCGGAUGCUUGGGGCUGCCCCGGCGCGCCCCCCUACAGGCGCGACCCGCUGAGUGACCCGGAGGGGGCCCGAGCUCGCCCCAGGAGGGGCCCCCGGCCUCGGGACCCCGCGCCGGACCUGCUGGGGAGCCGACGAUGUCCGCGCAGUCCCAGGCAUUGACGCGCUCGACGCAGCCCAGGGAAGGCGGCCGGCCGCUGCCCGCCGAGCCCUAGGCGCACAAAGCCCGCGCCCGCCGCCCGGCCCCGGCGCCCGCCGACGACUUUGCCGCCUGCUCCGCGGCUCUUUGUCUCCACUUGGGGCGGGCGCCCGACUCUGGGAUUUCGCUGCGAGAACGAGCUGGGGGGGCCGGGGGCGAGCUCUCGGUUUCCCGGCCGCCCCCCGCUCGGGCUCGGCUCCCCCCUCCCCCGCACCUCCCCGGCCCGGGCUCUCGGCGCUUCCACGCUCUCGGAAUCACGACCCCUCCCUGCCAUGUAUCCGCAGGGCAGACAUCCGGCUCCCCAUCAACCCGGGCAGCCGGGAUUUAAAUUCACGGUGGCUGAGUCUUGUGACAGGAUCAAAGACGAAUUCCAGUUCCUGCAAGCUCAGUAUCACAGCCUCAAAGUGGAGUACGACAAGCUGGCAAACGAGAAGACGGAGAUGCAGCGCCAUUAUGUGAUGUACUAUGAGAUGUCCUAUGGCUUGAACAUUGAAAUGCACAAGCAGACAGAGAUUGCGAAGAGACUGAACACAAUUUUAGCACAGAUCAUGCCUUUCCUGUCACAAGAGCACCAGCAGCAGGUGGCGCAGGCAGUGGAGCGCGCCAAGCAGGUCACCAUGACGGAGCUGAACGCCAUCAUCGGGGUACGUGGACUCCCCAAUCUGCCUCUUACCCAGCAGCAGCUCCAGGCGCAGCACCUCUCCCAUGCCACACACGGCCCCCCGGUCCAGUUGCCACCCCACCCGUCAGGUCUCCAGCCUCCAGGAAUCCCCCCAGUGACAGGGAGCAGCUCCGGGCUGCUGGCACUGGGCGCCCUGGGCAGCCAGGCCCAUCUGACGGUGAAGGAUGAGAAGAACCACCAUGAACUCGAUCACAGAGAGAGAGAAUCCAGUGCGAAUAACUCUGUGUCACCCUCGGAAAGCCUCCGGGCCAGUGAGAAGCACCGGGGCUCUGCGGACUACAGCAUGGAAGCCAAGAAGCGGAAGGCGGAGGAGAAGGACAGCUUGAGCCGAUACGACAGUGAUGGAGACAAGAGUGAUGAUCUGGUGGUGGAUGUUUCCAAUGAGGACCCCGCAACGCCCCGGGUCAGCCCGGCACACUCCCCUCCUGAAAAUGGGCUGGACAAGGCCCGUAGCCUGAAAAAAGAUGCCCCCACCAGCCCUGCCUCGGUGGCCUCUUCCAGUAGCACACCUUCCUCCAAGACCAAAGACCUUGGUCAUAACGACAAAUCCUCCACCCCUGGGCUCAAGUCCAACACACCAACCCCAAGGAACGACGCCCCAACUCCAGGCACCAGCACGACCCCAGGGCUCAGGUCGAUGCCGGGUAAACCUCCGGGCAUGGACCCGAUAGGUAUAAUGGCCUCGGCUCUGCGCACGCCCAUCUCCAUCACCAGCUCCUAUGCGGCGCCCUUCGCCAUGAUGAGCCACCAUGAGAUGAACGGCUCCCUCACCAGUCCUGGCGCCUACGCCGGCCUCCACAACAUCCCACCCCAGAUGAGCGCCGCCGCCGCUGCUGCAGCCGCUGCCUAUGGCCGAUCGCCAAUGGUGAGCUUUGGAGCUGUUGGUUUUGACCCUCACCCCCCGAUGCGGGCCACAGGCCUCCCCUCAAGCCUGGCCUCCAUUCCUGGAGGAAAACCAGCGUACUCAUUCCAUGUGAGUGCUGAUGGGCAGAUGCAGCCCGUGCCCUUCCCCCACGACGCCCUGGCAGGCCCCGGCAUCCCGAGGCACGCCCGGCAGAUCAACACACUCAGCCACGGGGAGGUGGUGUGUGCCGUGACCAUCAGCAACCCCACGAGGCACGUCUACACAGGUGGCAAGGGCUGCGUGAAGAUCUGGGACAUCAGCCAGCCAGGCAGCAAGAGCCCCAUCUCCCAGCUGGACUGCCUGAACAGGGACAAUUACAUCCGCUCCUGCAAGCUGCUCCCUGAUGGGCGCACGCUCAUCGUGGGCGGCGAGGCCAGCACGCUCACCAUCUGGGACCUGGCCUCGCCCACGCCCCGCAUCAAGGCCGAGCUGACGUCCUCGGCUCCCGCCUGUUAUGCCCUGGCCAUUAGCCCUGACGCCAAAGUCUGCUUCUCCUGCUGCAGCGAUGGGAACAUUGCUGUCUGGGACCUGCACAACCAGACCCUGGUCAGGCAGUUCCAGGGCCACACAGAUGGGGCCAGCUGCAUAGACAUCUCCCAUGAUGGCACCAAACUGUGGACAGGGGGCCUGGACAACACGGUGCGCUCCUGGGACCUGCGGGAGGGCCGACAGCUACAGCAGCAUGACUUCACUUCCCAGAUCUUCUCGCUGGGCUACUGCCCCACUGGGGAGUGGCUGGCUGUGGGCAUGGAGAGCAGCAACGUGGAGGUGCUGCACCACACCAAGCCUGACAAGUACCAGCUGCACCUGCACGAGAGCUGCGUGCUCUCCCUCAAGUUCGCCUACUGCGGCAAGUGGUUCGUGAGCACUGGGAAAGAUAACCUUCUCAACGCCUGGAGGACGCCUUAUGGAGCCAGCAUAUUCCAGUCUAAAGAAUCCUCGUCUGUCUUGAGUUGUGACAUUUCAGCGGAUGACAAAUACAUUGUAACAGGCUCUGGUGACAAGAAGGCCACAGUUUAUGAGGUCAUCUACUAAACAAGAACUCCAGCAGGGCUGUCAAACUCUGGGAGAAACCGACUCGGCUCUGACAGGGAGACCCCCAGGCGAGGGGCCCCGAGGAUGGCGGAGGAUGGGCCGCAGGCAGCCGAGCGUUCAGGGCUGCGCUCCGGCCGGCUGAGAGGGCACGUGCCCCGUCACAGUCUGGACUCCUGGGCCUGGAUUGAUGUGUCUCACAGACUCGGAAGGGUUCUGCUCCUCCUCCUCCCCCUGAACAAUGCUGGCAGUUGCUACAAAUAGAUUUAUUGGAGGCUUAUGGCUCCGGUUCCCCCACAGACCCGCUCAUGAGUCUCUGUUUGUUCUUCCCUUUUCUUUUGCCCUGUCCCUCACCUUGGGUCGGGGGUGCUGGAGUGGACCACAAUGUUGUGCUGGGGGAUGGGGGGGUCUCUCUUUGCCGAUUGUGCAGUGCACAAGAUUUGUGAAAAAUGUAAAUAACAGACUCCUAUUGCGGACUGAUCAGUGGGAGAGGAGGCCCCUUCCCACCGGAAACUCUGAGUGUGUAUUUCGCCUGCUGUAUUUGUAAUCCACUCGUGGUGGUGGCUUUUUUUUUUUUUUUUUUUUAAAUAAACAGAUGCUCUCACCUGGGAAGAGGAGACAGGGAGGGGAACCAAUUGAAGAAAGAGGAGAAAAGUCUUAGAGUGUGGAAAAGGCAACCAGGUUGGCCGUAAGGUGCCUGCUGGAAUGCGUGUGCCUCCACACGGGUCUGGGCAUCCGGACUGAUAACCAGCCGGCCAGACUGAGGGAUGGAAGGCACUGAGAUGGGGGCCCGUCCAGGCGGACACCCGCAGAAAUGGAGCUUUCUGUGGUCUCUUGCACUCUGGCUGCCUCUUGCCCUCUCUGUGUCUCUCUUUCUUGGUCUCUCCCUCUCUCCUCCUCAGCCUGGUCUUUCUCUUUGGUGCACACUUAGUUAUUGUUGUGAGCAAUGGAAGUUCAAAGGAACUCCCUCUCCAGCUCUUCUGAAUCUUGGGACACAGCCUAAAAAGGACAAAAAGUUAGAAGACAGCAUAGCAACUCAGCUCAGGGAGCUACCAGAGAAAAAUAGCAACUGAUGUGGGUGCUUUUUUUUUUUUUUUAAUUUGAAUAAAAAGAAUUAGAAGUGAUGUCCUUUUAUAAAAUGCCUUCUCCCCCUUCCCGCCUACAGUCUCUUCCUCUCCCCUUAGAGGGGGGAAAGUGUAUAAACCUACAGGGUUGUGAGUCUGAAAAGAGGAUCCCCCUCACCCCCACCCUGGGCAGAGCAGUGGGGGUUGGGGGGUGGGAGAGGGGGACACAGAUCCUGGCACACUGUGGAUAUUUCUUGCAGAUUGCAGUCUCUUGUGGCCCAAACAGGUUAGGUAGACUAUCGCCUCUGGCAGGUGCCACCUUUUGGUACCAACAUGUUCUGAGGUGUUAGGAUUUGGGUUGGGUUUUUUUUGUUUGUUUUUUUUUUCCUUUUGGUCUUUUUUUUUUUCUCCUUUUAAAGAAAAGCUAAAGGCCGCUGUGAGUCCUGGUGGCAGGCUCUCCAUGGAUGUAGCAUAUCGAAGAUAAUUUUUAUACUGCAUUUUUAUGGAUUAUUUUGUAAUGUGUGAUUCCGUCUGCUGAGGAGGUGGGAGGGGCUCCAGGGAAAGCCACCCACCUUCAGUGAGGUUGCUCCCCAGCUGAGCGCACCGGGCAUGGGAUGUGGAGGCUGGCGACACACCCUGUGCCUCUCCAAGGCUGGGCGCGUGGGGCGUCCAGAGUCUCUCUGGGUCUCAGAUGUCCAUCUGCCACCUCUUGUUAAGGCUCUAGCCAGAAGGGAGGGUGAGGGUAGAAGAAAGUUAUUCCCGAAGAAAAAAAGAAUGAAAAGUCAUUGUACUGAACUGUUUUUAUAUUUUUAAAAGUUACUAUUUAAAGGUUGGUUUGAUUGUUGCGUCUUAAUUGCCUCUCCCCCCAGUUUGCCAGUCCCGCCCCCCGCCCCCCGGGAAAACAGCCAGGCCACUGUUGCUGUCACAUUCUGGAGCCUGGGCCAGGGCCAUUUCCCAUCGAUGUGAGCUCUUCUCAUCUCACAGCAUUCCCUGCGCUGCUUCCACCCCCUUCUCCCCUUCCAGAUACCCAGCAUCGCAGCAGGGAUUUCACAAUCCCAUACUGUGUCGCCUCCCAUCCAAGCGCCAGGGAGGGUGGGGGGUAGGAGCUAAGACUUCCUCUGGACAGAUGGGCAGGGCAGAGUUCACUGAGGUGAAGGAAGACCACAGGUUAACACCAAAGUAUUGUACAGCUGUCAAUGCAAAACUUUUUUGGAAAAAAAUUAAACGUAAUGAACUUGAAGCGAAA